GCAUUUUCUUUUGAUAGUAGCCGUAGAGAAGUUGUCCGCCAGGCAGCCCUCAAUGGGAUUUUUCAUUUAAGAAAAAUCACUCUGCUCGUGCACUGAUGGAGAAAUGAACUACAAGAAGCAAGCCCUGAGGUCUGGAGACAGGAAGCUACUGAAACCAGCCAGGGAGUGAGCCAUAACUGGUGGCUGCUCUUGCGCCAAUGAGCCUCCCCAAUUCCUCCUGCCUCUUAGAAGACAAGAUGUGUGAGGGCAACAAGACCACUAUGGCCAGCCCCCAGCUGAUGCCCCUGGUGGUGGUCCUGAGCACUAUCUGCUUGGUCACAGUAGGGCUCAACCUGCUGGUGCUGUAUGCCGUACGGAGUGAGCGGAAGCUCCACACUGUGGGGAACCUGUACAUCGUCAGCCUCUCGGUGGCGGACUUGAUCGUGGGUGCCGUCGUCAUGCCUAUGAACAUCCUCUACCUGCUCAUGUCCAAGUGGUCACUGGGCCGUCCUCUCUGCCUCUUUUGGCUUUCCAUGGACUAUGUGGCCAGCACAGCGUCCAUUUUCAGUGUCUUCAUCCUGUGCAUUGAUCGCUACCGCUCUGUCCAGCAGCCCCUCAGGUACCUUAAGUAUCGUACCAAGACCCGAGCCUCGGCCACCAUUCUGGGGGCCUGGUUUCUCUCUUUUCUGUGGGUUAUUCCCAUUCUAGGCUGGAAUCACUUCAUGCAGCAGACCUCGGUGCGCCGAGAGGACAAGUGUGAGACAGACUUCUAUGAUGUCACCUGGUUCAAGGUCAUGACUGCCAUCAUCAACUUCUACCUGCCCACCUUGCUCAUGCUCUGGUUCUAUGCCAAGAUCUACAAGGCCGUACGACAACACUGCCAGCACCGGGAGCUCAUCAAUAGGUCCCUCCCUUCCUUCUCAGAAAUUAAGCUGAGGCCAGAGAACCCCAAGGGGGAUGCCAAGAAACCAGGGAAGGAGUCUCCCUGGGAGGUUCUGAAAAGGAAGCCAAAAGAUGCUGGUGGUGGAUCUGUCUUGAAGUCACCAUCCCAAACCCCCAAGGAGAUGAAAUCCCCAGUUGUCUUCAGCCAAGAGGAUGAUAGAGAAGUAGACAAACUCUACUGCUUUCCACUUGAUAUUGUGCACAUGCAGGCUGCGGCAGAGGGGAGUAGCAGGGACUAUGUAGCCGUCAACCGGAGCCAUGGCCAGCUCAAGACAGAUGAGCAGGGCCUGAACACACAUGGGGCCAGCGAGAUAUCAGAGGAUCAGAUGUUAGGUGAUAGCCAAUCCUUCUCUCGAACGGACUCAGAUACCACCACAGAGACAGCACCAGGCAAAGGCAAAUUGAGGAGUGGGUCUAACACAGGCCUGGAUUACAUCAAGUUUACUUGGAAGAGGCUCCGCUCGCAUUCAAGACAGUAUGUAUCUGGGUUGCACAUGAACCGCGAAAGGAAGGCCGCCAAACAGUUGGGUUUUAUCAUGGCAGCCUUCAUCCUCUGCUGGAUCCCUUAUUUCAUCUUCUUCAUGGUCAUUGCCUUCUGCAAGAACUGUUGCAAUGAACAUUUGCACAUGUUCACCAUCUGGCUGGGCUACAUCAACUCCACACUGAACCCCCUCAUCUACCCCUUGUGCAAUGAGAACUUCAAGAAGACAUUCAAGAGAAUUCUGCAUAUUCGCUCCUAAGGGAGGCUCUGAGGGGAUGCAACAAAAUGAUCCUUAUGAUGUCCAACAAGGAAAUAGAGGACGAAGGCCUGUGUGUUGCCAGGCAGGCACCUGGGCUUUCUGGAAUCCAAACCACAGUCUUAGGGGCUUGGUAGUUUGGAAAGUUCUUAGGCACCAUAGAAGAACAGCAGAUGGCGGUGAUCAGCAGAGAGAUUGAACUUUGAGGAGGAAGCAGAAUCUUUGCAAGAAAGUCAGACCUGUUUCUUGUAACUGGGUUCAAAAAGAAAAAAAUAAUAAAAAUAAAAGAGAGAGAGAAUCAGACCUGGGUGGAACUCUCCUGCUCCUCAGGAACUAUGGGAGCCUCAGACUCAUUGUAAUUCAAGCUUUCCGAGUCAAGUGAUUGACAACUGAAGAGACACGUGGCUAGGGUUCCACUGGAGAAUUGAAAAGGACUCUUGAGCCCUCCUGGAAUGGAGCUGUAUAACUGUGCAGAGACUUUAUCCAUGCCAAUAGUUGCUGUCCCCUUCCAGGGGUCACCUUGAGAGGCAUGACAGCUGUUCCACAGGGGCUAUCCCUUCUCAGAAAACUUCUCUUCUGAGCCUCUUUAACAGCUUUCUCCAGAACCAGUGUCUGAACCACCCUGGAAAUUCUGCCUUAUUAUUUCUUACUCAAACAUGUUUAGAGUGGAUAGAAAAUUAUGCAGCUUGCACACCCAUCGUCUUUAACCCCAAAUUUCCUUUGGCUAUUAAAAAAGUGGUGGCAAAAGACAUCCUCAAAAGAAAGAGAAAUGAAAUAUUUUUGAAUGGUUGCACGUUAAAAAUUAAAAGAAGGAAUGGGGGCAGAAUGCCAUAUUUUUGAGGGCUGUACUAGGUUUAUCUCAUUUAAGCCCCACAACACCCCACAGGAGGGUAAUUUUCUAACUCUAGUUUGCAGAGGAGCAAAUUGAGGUUCAGCAAGGUGAGAGAGGUACCCAAGGUCACAUAGCUAGUUAUGUGAGAAAGUUAGAGUACAGAUCCUCUGGGGUUUCAGCUUAUUGUAGCAUAUUUUCUCCGAAAGGCAAAAAUGUGCCCUUUUGGCCGGGCAUGGUAGCUCAAGCCUAUAAUCCCAGCAUGUUGAGAGGCUGAGGUGGGCAGAUCAUUUGAGGCCAGGAGUUCAAGACCAGUCUGGCCAAUAUGGAGAAACCUUGUCUCUACUAAAAACACAAAAAUUAUCUGGGCAUGGUGGGGCAUGCCUGUAGUCCCACUUACUUGGGAGGCCGAGGCACGAGAAUUGCUUGAACCCGGGAGGUGGAGGUUGCCGUGAGCCAAGAUCACGCCACUGCACUCCAGCCUGGGCAACAGAGCAAGACUCUGUCUCAAAAAAAAAAAUACAAUAUUUUAACAAUGUGCCCUCUUAAGUGUGCACAGAUACACAUACACGGUAUUCCCAAGAGUGGUGGCAGCUCAAAAUGAUAUGUUUGAGUAGACGAACAGCUGACAUGGAGUUCCCGUGCACCUACGGAAGGGGACGCUUUGAAGGAACCAAGUGCAUUUUUAUCUGUGAGUUCUGUUGUGUUUGUCAAAAAGUCAUUGUAAUCUUUCAUAGCCAUACCUGGUAAGCAAAAACUAGUAAAGACAUAGGAACAUGUAGUUUUACUUGGUGUUUAUGUUGCAAUCUGGUUGUGAUUUAUAUUUUAAAGCUUGGUGCUAAACCACAAUAUGUAUAGCAUAUGGAGUGCCUGUACAAGCUGAUGUUUUGUAUUUUGUGUUCCUCUUUGCAUGAUCUGUCAAAGUGAGAUAUUUUUACCUGCCUAAAAUAUGAUGUUUAAAAGCAUACUCUAUGUGAUUUAUUUAUUUCUACCUUUCUGAGUCUCUUGGACUAAGAAGAUGUUUUGAAAUGUACCAUCAAAUGUUAACAGAGUUUGAUAUGGGCUUUCUCUUUGGUUUCUCAUCACAUUUGUAAAUGUCUUUUCAAAAGGAUUUACUUUUUGUAAAAAGCUUCAUUCUCACUCUGCUUUGCAUCCCCCAAACUUCUUGUUCAAAACGGGGGGAGUUUAGGAGACUUUAAUCCCGGUUUCAGAAGCUGCAGCUGGUCUGUUUCCAGGUCAGAAACCAUUGUUCAGAAGACCUCCCUGUGAGAGAGUUGCUCCUCAGGGUCCCUCAGGACCAAAGAACACUCGAAAAGAGCACUUCACACAGACAAGUGGCUAAGUGUCCAUUAUUUACCUUGAACAAUCAAGGCAACUAGUGGAGAGAACUGAUUGUGAGCUCUGCCUCUGGGUCAGAGAGACCUGGAUUUGAGUCUGACAAGAACAAGAAAUGGUCAAUAAAUAUAAAUUACCAGCGUCUAAGGAACAAGGUCUAUGCAUUAUUGUAUACAGUGUCUCUAGUGCUUGUAUAGUGUCUGGUAUACAGAGGGCACUCCUAUGCAUUUUUAAAACAUGCUGAGCACAUACCAUGUGCCAGGCUUUGUGUUUUAUCUAAUGUUAUCUAAUGGUAUUGGUGCCAUUAUGUAAUGUUGCCUUUACAACAACCUCAUGAGGGAGAUUUCCAUCUUUACAAAUAGGCAAACUGAGGCCCAGAGAGAUUGAGGAACUGCUCCGAGGUCUGAUUCUGGAAUGUGCUUCCUUUCCACUUUAUCAAUCUGCUCUUCGUACUCCUGUCUGAACGAUGGAAAUUAAUUUUUGAAUGUAUAAAAGACAACAGACUAUGAUACAGAAAUGUCAGCCCCAGCCCACUAAGAAAGCCCCAGCCCAUCAGUGGCUAAUGGCUUUAAUAAAUUGGUCAUUUGGCUACUUGGCUUGUGGACAAUCUCUGACCUCUUUUGAAGAUGGGCACUGCAUGGACUUCCAGGAGGUGGAUUUAAUAGUCUUAACUCAGCAUGAAAAAGAUGCUGGGAUGCUCCUGGCUAUUUAUGCACCCUAAGUGCCAUAGAGACAUGCUGUUGGCAAGGCAUGGUGGCUCAUGCCUGUAAUCCCAGCACACUGGGAGGCUGACGCGGGCAGAUGGCUGGAGUCCAGGAGUUCGAGACAAGCCUGGGCACCAUGGUGAAAUCCUGUCUCUACUAAAAAUAAAAAAUUAGCCAGGGGCUGUGACGCA